AAAUCCAGAGCGGCGGGCACUGACGGGCACUUGCACCGUGUGGACAGACUCUCCGGUUCUGGGGAAAUCCAGUCCCUGUUACUCCAUUUUGGCCAGAAAUUCAAGACAUUUCAGGUGGCAGAAUAAAUUCAAUCCUUGUUUCUCCAUCUUAUCGAGUAGUAGAAGUUAGUUACAUUCUCUUUGAACUCAUCAUGAAUUCCAUGAAGACUGAAGAAAACAAGUCAUUUAGCGCUAUGGAAGAUGACCAGAGGACUAGACCUGAAGUUUCAAAGGAUACUGUCAUGAAGCAGACACAUGCUGACACACCUGUUGAUCAUUGUCUAUCUGGCAUAAGAAAGUGUAGCAGCACCUUUAAGCUUAAAAGUGAAGUCAACAAGCAUGAAACAGCCCUUGAAAUGCAGAAUCCAAAUUUGAACAAUAAAGAAUGUUGUUUCACCUUUACGUUGAAUGGAAACUCCAGAAAAUUAGACCGUAGUGUGUUUACAGCAUAUGGUAAACCCAGCGAGAGUAUCUACUCAGCCCUGAGUGCUAAUGACUAUUUCAGUGAAAGGAUAAAGAAUCAGUUUAAUAAGAACAUUAUUGUUUAUGAAGAAAAGACAAUAGAUGGACAUAUAAAUUUAGGAAUGCCUCUCAAGUGCCUGCCUAGUGAUUCUCAUUUUAAAAUUACAUUUGGUCAAAGAAAGAGUAGCAAAGAAGAUGGACACAUAUUACGCCAAUGUGAAAAUCCAAACAUGGAAUGCAUUCUUUUUCAUGUUGUUGCUAUAGGAAGGACAAGAAAGAAGAUUGUUAAGAUCAACGAACUUCAUGAAAAAGGAAGUAAACUUUGUAUUUAUGCCUUGAAGGGUGAGACUAUUGAAGGAGCCUUAUGCAAGGAUGGCCGUUUUCGGUCUGACAUAGGUGAAUUUGAAUGGAAACUAAAGGAAGGUCAUAAGAAAAUUUAUGGAAAACAGUCCAUGGUGGAUGAAGUAUCUGGAAAAGUCUUAGAAAUGGACAUUUCAAAAAAAAAAGCAUUACAACAGAAAGAUAUCCAUAAAAAAAUUAAACAGAAUGAAAGUGCCACUGAUGAAAUUAAUCACCAGAGUCUGAUACAGUCUAAGAAAAAAGUCCACAAACCAAAGAAAGAUGGAGAGACCAAAGAUGUAGAACACAGCAGAGAGCAAAUUCUCCCACCUCAGGAUCUAAGCCAUUAUAUUAAAGAUAAAACUCGCCAGACAAUUCCCAGGAUUAGAAAUUAUUACUUUUGUAGUUUGCCCCGAAAAUAUAGGCAAAUAAACUCACAAGUUAGACGGAGGCCGCAUCUGGGUAGGCGGUAUGCUAUUAAUCUGGAUGUCCAAAAGGAGGCAAUUAAUCUCUUAAAGAAUUAUCAAACGUUGAAUGAAGCCAUAAUGCAUCAGUAUCCGAAUUUUAAAGAGGAGGCACAGUGGGUAAGAAAAUAUUUUCGGGAAGAACAAAAGAGAAUGAAUCUUUCACCAGCUAAGCAAUUCAACAUAUAUAAAAAGGACUUCGGAAAAAUGACUGCAAAUUCUGUUUCAGUUGCAACCUGCGAACAGCUUACAUAUUAUAGCAAGUCAGUUGGGUUCAUGCAAUGGGACAAUAAUGGAAACACAGGUAAUGCUACUUGCUUUGUCUUCAAUGGUGGUUAUAUUUUCACCUGUCGACAUGUUGUACAUCUUAUGGUGGGUAAAAACACACAUCCAAGUUUGUGGCCAGAUAUAAUUAGCAAAUGUGCGAAGGUAACCUUCACUUAUACAGAGUUCUGCCCUACUCCUGACAAUUGGUUUUCCAUUGAGCCAUGGCUUAAAGUGUCCAAUGAAAAUCUAGAUUAUGCCAUUUUAAAACUAAAAGAAAAUGGAAAUGCGUUUCCUCCAGGACUAUGGCGACAGAUUUCUCCUCAACCAUCUACUGGUUUGAUUUAUUUAAUUGGUCAUCCUGAAGGCCAGAUCAAGAAAAUAGAUGGUUGUACUGUGAUUCCUCUAAACGAACGAUUGAAAAAAUAUCCAAACGAUUGUCAAGAUGGGUUGGUAGAUCUCUAUGAUACCACCAGUAAUGUAUACUGUAUGUUUACCCAAAGAAGUUUCCUAUCAGAGGUUUGGAACACACACACGCUUAGUUAUGAUACUUGUUUCUCUGAUGGGUCCUCAGGCUCCCCAGUGUUUAAUGCAUCUGGCAAAUUGGUUGCUUUGCAUACCUUUGGGCUUUUUUAUCAACGAGGAUUUAAUGUGCAUGCCCUUAUUGAAUUUGGUUAUUCUAUGGAUUCUAUUCUUUGUGAUAUUAAAAAGACAAAUGAGAGCUUGUAUAAAUCAUUAAAUGAUGAGAAACUUGAGACCUACGAUGAAGAGAAAGGUAAACAAGAGUCAUCACUUCAAGAUCAUCAGAUUGAACCCAUGGAAUGUUAGAAAAGAGAUGCUGUCUUCAAGAAAAUAUGCCAAUAAUUCCUGGCAAAGAUUUCAUGACAAAGACACUUAAAGCAAUUGCAACAAAAGUGAAAAUUGGCAAAUGAGACCUAAUUAAAUCUUCUGCACAGCAAAAGAAACUAUCAACAGGGUAAACACACAACCUACGGAAUGGGAGAAAAUAUUUGCAAACUAUGCAUACAGCAAAGAUCUAAUAUUCAGAAUCCAUUAGGAACUUAAACAGAUUAACAAGCAAAAAAAACAAGCAACCCCAUUAAAAAGUGGGCAAAGGACAUGAACAAACACUUUUCAAAAGAAGAUAUACACAUGGCCAACAAGGAUAUGAAAAAAUACCUGAUAUCACUAAUCAUUAGAGAAAUGCAAAUCAAAAAAAUGCCAUCACACUAAUCAGAAUGGCUGUUAUUAAAAUGCCAAAAAAUUACAGAUGCUGGCGAGGUUGCAGAGAAAGGGGAAUGCUUAUACACUGCUAGUGGGAAAAUAAAUUAGUUCAGCCAUUGUGGAAAGCAGUUGGGUGAUUUCUAAAAGAACUUAAAACAGCUACCAUUCAAGCCAGCAAUCUCAUGACUGGGUAUAUGUCCAAAGGAAUAUAAAUUGUUCUACCAUAAAGACAUGCACAUAUAUGUUCACUGCAGCACUAUUCACAAUAGCAAAACAUGAAAUCAACCUAAAUGCCCAUCAAUGGUAGACUGGAUAAAGAAAAUGUGACACAUAUACACCAUAGCAUACUACACAGCCAUAAAAAAGUACAAGAUCAUGUGCUUUGCAGCAACAUGGAUGGAACUGAAGGUCAUUAUCCUAAGCGAACUAAUGCAGGAACAGAAAGCCAAGUACCACAUGUUCUCUCAUAAGUGGAAGCUAAAUAUUGAGUACACAUGGACACAAAGAAGAAAACAACAGAUAUGGGGCCUACUUGAGGGUGGAGGGUGGGAGGAGGGUGAAGACUGAAAAACUGCCUAUGGGGUACUAUGCUUAUUACCUGGGUGAUGAAAUAAUCUGAACACAAAACCCUGGUGACAUGCAGUUUACCUAUAUAACAAAACUGCACAUGGACUCUUAAACCUAAAUAAAAGUUUAAAAUAUAUAUAAUGCCAA